UGAAGUAGAUACACUGGCUAUUCUGGUUCCUGUAACAGUGGCCAUUCCUAACCCUAUAAGUAGGGGUAUUAGUUGUAUUGCUCUGCACUGACAGACUUGAGCUUUGAGGUGCACUGAUAGGGUCUGAUUUCCUGGGGCAAUGUCAAUGUUGGGACUUAGGAAGACUAAGGUGCAGGUGCCUGUCCAGUUGGUGGGGAGGCAGAUAUAGGUUGAAGUUCCACAUAAGAAGAAUAUGCCUUGGCUGGGUACACAGAACUGGUUGUGUAUGUUAAAAAGGAAGGAGGUGAUGAUUUUUGGAGGCUCUGAGAAGCGGACAAGCCAUCUGAAUGGAGCUGUUUGGCUGUAGAAACUGAGGCUCAGAGAGAAGUGACUUUGAGCUCACAGUGUCACCGCCUGCUGAUGGGAGAGCUGAAUUCAAAACCAGCAGGGUGUCUCCCUGAGCAGAGGGACCUGCACACAGAGACUCCCUCCUGGGCUCCUGGCACCAUGGCCCCACUGAAGAUGCUGGCCCUGGUCACCCUCCUCCUGGGGGCUUCUCUGCAGCACAUCCACGCAGCUCGAGGGACCAAUGUGGGCCGGGAGUGCUGCCUGGAGUACUUCAAGGGAGCCAUUCCCCUUAGAAAGCUGAAGACGUGGUACCAGACAUCUGAGGACUGCUCCAGGGAUGCCAUCGUUUUUGUAACUGUGCAGGGCAGGGCCAUCUGUUCGGACCCCAACAACAAGAGAGUGAAGAAUGCAGUUAAAUACCUGCAAAGCCUUGAGAGGUCUUGAAGCCUCCUCACCCCAGACUCCUGACUGUCUCCCGGGACUACCUGGGACCUCCACCGUUGGUGUUCACCGCCCCCACCCUGAGCGCCUGGGUCCAGGGGAGGCCUUCCAGGGACGAAGAAGAGCCACAGUGAGGGAGAUCCCAUCCCCUUGUCUGAACUGGAGCCAUGGGCACAAAGGGCCCAGAUUAAAGUCUUUAUCCUCA